GUCUCCCCUCGCCGCAUCCACUCUCCGGCCGGCCGCCUGCCCGCCGCCUCCUCCGUGCGCCCGCCAGCCUCGCCCGCGCCGUCACCAUGAGCCAGGCCUACUCGUCCAGCCAGCGCGUGUCCUCCUACCGCCGCACCUUCGGCGGGGCCCCGGGCUUCCCACUCGGCUCCCCGCUGAGUUCGCCCGUGUUCCCGCGGGCGGGUUUCGGCUCUAAGGGCUCCUCCAGCUCGGUGACGUCCCGCGUGUACCAGGUGUCGCGCACGUCGGGCGGGGCCGGGGGCCUGGGGUCGCUGCGGGCCAGCCGGCUGGGGACCACCCGCACGCCCUCCUCCUACGGCGCAGGCGAGCUGCUGGACUUCUCACUGGCCGACGCGGUGAACCAGGAGUUUCUGACCACGCGCACCAACGAGAAGGUGGAGCUGCAGGAGCUCAAUGACCGCUUCGCCAACUACAUCGAGAAGGUGCGCUUCCUGGAGCAGCAGAACGCGGCGCUCGCCGCCGAAGUGAACCGGCUCAAGGGCCGCGAGCCGACGCGAGUGGCCGAGCUCUACGAGGAGGAGCUGCGGGAGCUGCGGCGCCAGGUGGAGGUGCUCACUAACCAGCGCGCGCGCGUCGACGUCGAGCGCGACAACCUGCUCGACGACCUGCAGCGGCUCAAGGCCAAGCUGCAGGAGGAGAUUCAGUUGAAGGAAGAAGCAGAGAACAAUUUGGCUGCCUUCCGAGCGGACGUGGAUGCAGCUACUCUAGCUCGCAUUGACCUGGAGCGCAGAAUUGAAUCUCUCAACGAGGAGAUCGCGUUCCUUAAGAAAGUGCAUGAAGAGGAGAUCCGUGAGUUGCAGGCUCAGCUUCAGGAACAGCAGGUCCAGGUGGAGAUGGACAUGUCUAAGCCAGACCUCACUGCCGCCCUCAGGGACAUCCGGGCUCAGUAUGAGACCAUCGCGGCUAAGAACAUUUCUGAAGCUGAGGAGUGGUACAAGUCGAAGGUGUCAGACCUGACCCAGGCAGCCAACAAGAACAACGACGCCCUGCGCCAGGCCAAGCAGGAGAUGAUGGAAUACCGACACCAGAUCCAGUCCUACACCUGCGAGAUUGACGCCCUGAAGGGCACUAACGAUUCCCUGAUGAGGCAGAUGCGGGAAUUGGAGGACCGAUUUGCCAGUGAGGCCAGUGGCUACCAGGACAACAUUGCGCGCCUGGAGGAGGAAAUCCGGCACCUCAAGGAUGAGAUGGCCCGCCAUCUGCGCGAGUACCAGGACCUGCUCAACGUGAAGAUGGCCCUGGAUGUGGAGAUUGCCACCUACCGGAAGCUGCUGGAGGGAGAGGAGAGCCGGAUCAAUCUCCCCAUCCAGACCUACUCUGCCCUCAACUUCCGAGAAACCAGCCCUGAGCAAAGGGGUUCUGAGGUCCAUACCAAGAAGACGGUGAUGAUCAAGACCAUCGAGACACGGGAUGGGGAGGUCGUCAGUGAGGCCACACAGCAGCAGCAUGAAGUGCUCUAAAGACAGAGACCCUCUGCCACCAGAGACCGUCCUCACCCCUGUCCUCACUGCUCCCUGAAGCCAGCCUUCUUCCAUCCCAGGACACCACACCCAGCCUCAGUCCUCCCCUCACAGCCUCUGACCCCUCCUCACUGGCCAUCCCUCGUGGUCCCCAACAGCGACAUAGCCCAUCCCUGCCUGGUCACAGGGCAUGCCCCGGCCACCUCUGCGGACCCCAGCUGUGAGCCUUGGCUGUUGGCAGUGAGUGAGCCUGGCUCUUGUGCUGGAUGGAGCCCAGGCGGGAGCGGUGGCCCUGUCCCUCCCACCUCUGUGACCUCAGGCACUAGCCUUUGGCUCUGGAGACAGCCCCAGAGCAGGGUGUUGGGAUACUGCAGGGCCAGGACUGAGCCCCGCAGACCUCCCCAGCCCCUAGCCCAGGAGAGAGAAAGCCAGGCAGGUAGCCAGGGGGACUAGCCCCUGUGGAGACUGGGGGGCUUGAAAUUGUCCCCGUGGUCUCUUACUUUCCUUUCCCCAGCCCAGGGUGGACUUAGAAAGCAGGGGCUACAAGAGGGAAUCCCCGAAGGUGCUGGAGGUGGGAGCAGGAGAUUGAGAAGGAGAGAAAGUGGGUGAGAUGCUGGAGAAGAGAGGAGAGGAGAGAGGCAGAGAGCGGUCUCAGGCUGGUGGGAGGGGCGCCCACCUCCCCACGCCCUCCCCUCCCCUGCUGCAGGGGCUCUGGAGAGAAACAAUAAAGAGAUUCACACACAA